GCAGAUGGCUGAGAGCUAGCAAGGAAAACUCAGGACCAUGAUGGCUCAGUUUCCCACAGCUAUGAAUGGUAAGCAGCUUUGUGCUUGUGGCAAGAUGAGGUUAUGGAUUUUUUUUUUUUUUGGUAGAGGUUUAAAAUAUUCAUGUAGAUAAUUUUCCUUAAGUGUAUAAAUACAAAACUUGAAGUAUUCUUGGAAAAUAUUUUGGAACACUGCAUAUGUCUUCUGUAAGAAUAUUAUGUUGUAAAUCCCAUGACUAUAUUCUGGAACGUGUGUUUGCCAUUGAGCAGUUAGGAAUAACCAAAAGGUAUAUUGUGUUUGAUGCAUAAAACUGGAUGACAAAUAGCAGAGUGCUAUAAGGUGACUAUUAAAGGUAUUUUGAUAACAUAACAUGAUUGUAAACCGAUGAAGCCAAUAAAGAUUAAUUUAGUAAUAUUUAUGUAAGAUUAUGUUUUCCCUUUAGAUAAGAUUAUGUAUGCCUGCAUACAUAAUUGUUUAAUAUCAAACAUUUUAAAAGAAAGUGCUGGCCGGGUGUGGUGGCUCAUGCCUGUAAUUACAGCACUUUGUGAGGCUGAGGAGGGAGAUCACUUGAGGUCAGGAGUUCGAGACCAGCCUGGUCAACAUGGUGAAACCCAAUCUCUACUAAAAAUACAAAAACUAGCCGAGUGUGGUCAUGGGCACCUGUAAUCCCAGCUGCUUGGGAGGUUGAGGCAGGAGAAUCACUUGAACUACCCGGGAGGUGGUGGUUGCAGUGUACCGAGAUAGGGCCACUACACUCCAGCCUGGGAAAGAGUGAGACUCCAUUUAAAAAAAAAAGAAAAAGAAAAAGAAAAAGAAAAUGCUUAGGUAAUUUGAAUAAUGAAAAGUUUUUAAAGUUUUGUUCUGAUUGUAGCUUUAAUUCUUUUCCCAAAUACUAAUUAACUACCCUUAGUAGGUAUUAAGUUACUGUGUUUGUCAUUUAUAAUUAAUUGAAAAACAUGCAUUAUAUUUUUAAAUCGCUAAAGAAAUCUAGAUUCUGAAUUCUUAAUUUUAUGUUAAAUUGUAUUAGCUAAUUGUAGAUAAAUAUCAGGAAAUAGAGAAUAAACUCAAUAAUUCUUUAUUAUUUAAAUUGAAAACAGUAAUAUUAAAGAGCAUUUAAAAAAAGGAGGGAAGAAUCACCAUUCUACCAUCUUCACAAAGCAAUUCUGUUUUGAUAUUACCGUCUAGUGUUAAUCAGUUGUUUUUUAAACUUGUUUUCAGACAUAGGACCAAAUCAUUACAUUGUUAAUAACGAAAAUACAUGUUGUAUAUCUAAAGUUUUAUGUCUCAGGAUUUAGGAAAAUCUUGGAGAAGUGAAUUAUUUGUAUAAAAAGUAAAAUCAAAUUCUGUGUGGUGAGGUCAUGUGUCAUUUAAGGAUAGACUUGAAGUAAAGAUUUUGUUGUUUCGUGUUUUACCUUUUCAGAACCUAUUAUUUAAGGAUUAAUGUGAGUAUUGCUCCUAUUGGGAAAAUGGUGUGGGAUUAUAAACAUUGAUGCCACAGACAAUUUUUAAUAAUUAAAUAAUUUUUCCAUAAUGAGUGAUACAUGUAAGUUUAAAAUUAGGGCAGUGAUUGUAGUAGUAACAUGCUCUACUCAAGUUUGAGGAUUUUUAUGCCCCAUACAAAGGAAUUUGCAUUAAACAGUUGAAUUGUAAACUUCAGCCAACAUGUUAAUCAGUUUUAUAAGCAAAAUGAACAUAAAGCAGUACAGUCCCGGUCCUUCUUUAUUCUGCUUCUUCCAUUCCAUAAACAUUUAUAUAUCUACUUUGCAGUUCAUUGCAUUAUAUAUAAAAUAUAACAUUGAGAACAAAUGGACUAUUCAAUAACAAAAGAAUGAUUAUGUGAAUAAUCAUCUAAAAUGUUGGAAAAUGCAUUUAGAAGUGCUAUAUAGGCAUACAGAUAGUAAUUUUUUUUAAACUUCUGAAGAAUUAAUUGCAUAUGUAGACUGUGGUACCUUCCUACUUAGAAGAUUGACGAUAACUUAGACAUAUCUAAUUUAAGUUCAAUUCAGGGUUUAAGAUGUUACUGAGAGCAGCAUUCAUGUAUAGUACAAAACUUUGCUCCUCUAGUAAUCCUGACAUAGAUUGUUAAAUUGUUUUGAUGCCCAUUGCUAUUGGGACUUGUCUGUAAGUAUGCCUGUGUGUGAAUGUGUAUGUGUGUGUGUAUGUGUGUGUGUGUAUGUAUAUACGUGUGUGUGUAAAAACCGAGAUGAGACUACUUACUGAAUGAGAUCUAGCCUAUAGUAGAUGUUCUGUAAAUGUGAAAAUUUUUUUCUUCACUGACUAUAAGAACUUGUUUGAAAGAGCCAGCAAGUGAGAUGAGAAUAAGCAACAGAAAUGUUUAUGAAAAUCCCAUAUUUUCAAUAUCAGUGAUGAGUUAGGGGAAGCGGAUAGAAUUUUAAUGUAUUUCUAACACGAUUAUUACAUAUUGUAAAAGUUUGUUAGCUUUUUAGGGAAAUAUUAGACAUCAACCCCUAAACUUAGAUUUUUCUGCCUCUUCGAUAAGGCUUACAGAUAAAUAUAGACUAAGAUUGGGAGAUUUUUACUUGAAGUUCAAAGUAACAAACUUUUGCCUUUUCAAAGGGUUCUGUUAGUUGAUAUAUUUAAAUAAGAAAGCCAGGACUGAAUUAACUAUUUUAAAAUUGGCUUUGAAUUACACGUAUUGCCCAGUUUUCUUAUUGCAGUGUUUUGUUUUUUGAGACAGGGUCUCCACUCUGUUGCCCAGGUUGGAGUGUAGUGGUAUGAACACAGCUCACUGCAGCCUCGACUUGCUAGAUUCAAGCAAUCCUCCUGCCUCUGCUUCCUGAGUAGCUGGGACCACAGGUGUGAGCCACCACACCCAGCUAAUUUUUAGAUUUUUUGUAGACAUGGGGGUCUCACUAUCUUGUCCAAGCUGGUCUUGAACUCUUGGGCUCAAGAAGUCCUCCACCUUAGCCUCCCAAAGUGCUUGGAUUACAGGCAUGAGCCAUCACACCUGACCAGUGUUAUCUUUUUGUUCCUAGAAAAUUCUUGGUGCAUUAAUACUUUAUGUUUUAAUAUGAUUAAUUUUUUAAAAGGUUAUUUGAACACUACUUAAAAAUUAUUCCUUGUUAAAAUGCCUUAGAACAUUUUUAUUCUCUUGGUUACAUUAAUCAUGAUAAUAUGUAACCGUGAUUGUUGUGUGUGAUUUUCUUGGCUGGUAGAGUCUCUUUAAAAUAUUAGAGUCUGUGAGUUCUUUUAAGGUGUUCAUUUUUUUUUUUUUUUUUUUUUUUUUUGAGACAGGGUCUUACUCUGUCAACCCAGCCUGGAGUACAGUGGCAUGAACAUUGCUCACUGCAAUCUCAACCUCCAGGCUCAAGCAAUUCCUUCUGCCUCAGCCUCCAGAGUAACUGGGACUACAGACAUGUGCCACCAAGACCAGCUACUUAAAAGAAUUUUUUUUUUAGAGAUAGGGGUCUCACUAUGUUGACCAGGCUGGUCUCAACUCCUGGGCUCAAGUGAUCCUCCUGCCCUAGCCUUCUGAAGUGCUGGGCUGUGCCCAGGCAAGUGGUUCAUUUUAUUCAUCUUUGUACCCCAUAAACAUUUACUGAAUGAAUGAAUAUGAAGGUGUCAAGAUUACUGAUUGGAGACAUGAGGAACUAAGCAGUAAACAAACAGAUGGGUUGAGUUUAGCCCCUGUGAAAACACAUAGCCAAGGAAAUGUCAGGAGAUAGUAAUAUAUAUAAGAAAGCAUCAUACUGUGAUGAGCAUUGGUGCAUCAAUCUUGAUGCAGCAGAACUCUCUUUUGUCUUAGGAUAGCAGUAGAGUCCAUCACUGCCCGGGGGUAUAUAUACCCAUGUAUGUUAGAGCAGCUUUUUAAAAAAAAUUUAAUUUAAUUUAAUUUAAUUUAAUUUUUUUGAGACGGAGUCUCGCUCUGUCUCCCAGGCUGGAGUGCAGUGGCAUGAUCUCUGCUCACUGCAAGCUCCGCCUACUGGGUUCACGCCGUUCUCCUGCCUCAGCCUCCCGAGUAGCUGGGACUACAGGCGCUCACCACCACGCCUAGCUAAGUUUUUGUAUUUUUAGUAGAGAUGGGGUUUCACCACGUUAGCCAGGAUGGUCUCCAUCUCCUGACCUCGUGAUCCACCCGCCUUGGCCUCCCAAAGUGCUGGGAUUACAGGUGUGAGCCACCAUGCCUGGCCGAGCAGCUUUUAAGCCUUCUUAACCAAACUCUUCAGACUUAAAAUAGUCUUAAGGUUUCUAACUAAAGAGCCUUAGUUUCAGGCUAUUCCCUGAGAAAGAUUUGAAUGCUCUGACUUCUUUUUAAUUAUAUUGUUCCCUGGGAUUGGGUUGAAUAAGGAAACUAAUUUAUUGAGGACUCCUAAUAUGGCAGGCAUGUAUUAGAUGCUUUAUAUUUUUGUUUUAGUUUAUUUUAAAGUUGGGUUUAUUGGGGGUAUAAUUCACCCUUUUAAAGUAUACGGUUCGAUGAGUUUCUAAAACUAUAUAUAGUCAUAUAAAUUAGGAUAUAAAACAUUUGCAUCACCUAAAAAGUUCUCUGUACCCUUAUACCUCCACCUUUAGCCAUGUAUUAUUGGCAACCACUAAUCAGAUUUCUGUCCUUACAGUUCUGCCUUUUCCAGAAUGUCAUAUAAAUGGAAUACACAAUAUGUAGCCUUUGGUGUCUGGCUUCUGUGACUUAGCAAAAUAUCUUUGUGAUUCAGUCAUAAUGUUGCAUGCAUUUCUCCUGUUUACUGCUGAAUAGUAGUCCAUUGUAUAAAUGUGUACCACAAUUUAUUUAUCCAUUCAGCCGUUCAGGUGCAGAACAUUUGGGUUAUUUCCAGGUUUUAGUGAUUAUGACUAAAUCUGCUAUAACCAUCAGAGAACAGGUUUUUAUGUGGAAAUAGGUCUUCGUUUCUCUUGGGUAUUUACCCAAGAGUCUUUUGUUAAUACUCAGUCUAUUGUUGGGUCAUGUGGAAAUAUAUAUUUAACUUCAUAAGAAAUUCCCAAACUGUUUUCCAAAGUGACUGUCACAUUUGCUUUCCCACCAGCAUAUAUGAGUUGCGGUUGUUUGGCAUCUUUAUCAGCACUCCGUGUUGUUUUUUUUUUUAAUUUUCAGACAUGCUAAUAGACAUGCAGUGAUACCUUUUUGUGAUUUUAAUUUACAUUUCCCUGAUGAUAGUGAUAUUGAGCAUCUUGUCACGUGCUUAUUUGCCAUCUGUAUAUCUUUGAUGUGUCUGUUCAAAUCUUUUGUUCCUUUUUUUUGAGGGGGGGGAUUAUUUUCUAAUUUUUGAGUUGAAUAGUUCUGUAUAUAUGCUGACCUAUAUUUAUUGAAUAUGUUUUGCAAAUGUUUUCUCUCAGCCUGUAGUUUGUCUUUUCCUUUUCUUAAGAGUGUCCUUUAAGAGAGUGGAAAUUUUAGAUUUUUAUAAAGUCCAGUUUGUCAAAAUAUUUUAAUGAUUUUUGCCUUUUGUGUUCCAAAAAGUCAUUGCAUAAUCCAAAAUCACAAACAUUUUCUUCCAUAUUUUCUUCAGGAAGUUUUAUCUUAUAUCUAGUUCUGUGAUUCAUUGAGAGUUAAUUCAUGUAUAUGCUGGAAGGUUGAGGUUCUUUUGUUGUUUUUUCAUAUGGAUAUCCAGUUCUUUCAGCACCAUUUGAUGAAAGGACUGUUUUCCACCUUGAAUUAUCUCCACAUGUUGUUGGAAAUCAAUGGACAAUAUAUUUGUUAAUGCUGGGGGCUCAGUGAGUUGCUGCAUAUAAAGUCCCUGACAAUAGUCAGGGUUCAAUAAAGGAGGGCCAAACAUGUGGGCUAUUACCUCUGAAGAACGUACUAAGCAUGACAGGCAGUUUGAUAACCUCAAACCUUCAGGAGGUUACAUAACAGGUGAUCAAGCACGUAAUUUUUUCCUACAAUCAGGUCUGCCGGCCCCUGUUUUAGCUGAAAUAUGGGCUUUAUCAGACCUAAACAAGGAUGGGAAGAUGGAUCAGCAAGAGUUCUCCAUAGCUAUGAAACUCAUCAAACUGAAGCUUCAAGGCCAACAGUUGCCUGUGGUUCUCCCUCCUAUUAUGAAGCAACCCCCUAUGUUUUCUCCAUUAAUUUCUGCUCGUUUUGGAAUGGGAAGCAUGCCCAAUCUGUCCAUUCCUCAGCCAUUGCCUCCAGCUGCACCUAUAACAUCAUUGUCUUCUGCGACUUCAGGGACCAACCUUCCUCCCUUAAUGAUGCCCACUCCCCUAGUGCCUUCUGUUAGCACAUCAUCAUUACCAAAUGGAACCGCCAGUCUCAUUCAGCCUUUACCCAUUCCUUAUUCUUCUUCAACAUUGCCUCAUGGGUCAUCUUAUAGUCUGAUGAUGGGAGGAUUUGGAGGUGCUAGUAUACAGAAAGCGCAGUCUCUGAUUGAUUUAGGAUCUAGUAGCUCAACUUCCUCGACUGCUUCACUCUCAGGGAACUCACCCAAGACUGGGACCUCAGAGUGGGCAGUUCCUCAGCCUACAAGAUUAAAAUAUCGGCAAAAAUUUAAUACUCUUGACAAAAGUAUGAGUGGAUAUCUCUCAGGUUUUCAAGCUAGAAAUGCCCUUCUUCAGUCAAAUCUUUCUCAAACUCAGCUGGCUACUAUUUGGACUCUGGCUGACGUUGAUGGUGAUGGACAGCUAAAAGCAGAAGAGUUUAUUCUUGCAAUGCACCUUACUGACAUGGCCAAAGCUGGACAGCCAUUACCACUGACUUUACCUCCUGAGCUUGUUCCUCCAUCUUUCAGAGGAGGAAAGCAAAUUGAUUCCAUUAAUGGAACUCUGCCUUCAUAUCAGAAAAUGCAAGAAGAGGAGCCUCAGAAGAAAUUACCAGUUACUUUUGAGGACAAACGGAAAGCCAACUAUGAGCGAGGGAACAUGGAGCUGGAAAAGCGACGCCAAGCCUUGAUGGAGCAGCAACAAAGGGAGGCAGAACGUAAAGCCCAGAAAGAAAAGGAAGAGUGGGAACGAAAACAGAGAGAAUUACAAGAACAAGAAUGGAAGAAACAACUUGAAUUAGAAAAACGCUUAGAGAAGCAACGGGAAUUGGAGAGACAACGAGAGGAAGAAAGGAGAAAAGACAUAGAAAGACGAGAGGCAGCAAAACAGGAACUUGAACGACAACGUCGCUUAGAAUGGGAGAGAAUUCGGCGACAGGAGCUUCUCAAUCAAAAGAAUAGAGAACAAGAAGAAAUUGUCAGGUUAAACUCUAAAAAGAAGAAUCUUCAUCUUGAGUUGGAAGCACUGAAUGGCAAACAUCAGCAGAUCUCAGGCAGACUUCAGGAUGUCCGACUCAAAAAGCAAACUCAAAAGACUGAGCUGGAAGUUCUGGAUAAGCAGUGUGACUUGGAAAUUAUGGAAAUCAAGCAACUUCAACAGGAACUUCAGGAAUAUCAGAAUAAGCUUAUCUAUCUGGUACCUGAGAAGCAAUUAUUAAAUGAAAGAAUUAAAAACAUGCAGUUCAGUAACACACCUGAUUCAGGGGUCAGUUUACUUCAUAAAAAAUCAUUAGAAAAGGAAGAAUUAUGCCAAAGACUUAAAGAACAGUUAGAUGCUCUUGAAAAAGAAACUGCAUCUAAGCUGUCAGAAAUGGAUUCUUUUAACAAUCAACUAAAGUGUGGGAAUAUGGAUGACUCUGUUCUUCAGUGCCUUUUGUCUCUGCUAAGCUGUCUCAACAACCUCUUCCUCUUACUUAAGGAACUGAGAGAAACCUACAACACACAGCAGUUAGCCCUUGAACAGCUUUAUAAGAUCAAACGUGACAAGUUGAAGGAAAUUGAAAGGAAAAGAUUAGAACUAAUGCAGAAAAAGAAACUAGAAGAUGAGGCUGCAAGGAAAGCAAAGCAAGGAAAAGAAAACUUAUGGAAAGAAAAUCUUAGAAAGGAGGAAGAAGAAAAACAAAAGCGACUCCAGGAAGAAAAAACACAAGAAAAAAUUCAAGAAGAGGAACGGAAAGCUGAGGAGAAACAACGUAAGGAUAAGGAUACUUUGAAAGCUGAGGAGAAAAAACGUGAGACAGCUAGUGUUUUGGUGAAUUAUAGAGCAUUAUACCCCUUUGAAGCAAGGAACCAUGAUGAGAUGAGUUUUAAUUCUGGAGAUAUAAUUCAGGUUGAUGAAAAAACCGUAGGAGAACCUGGUUGGCUUUAUGGUAGUUUUCAAGGAAAUUUUGGCUGGUUUCCAUGCAAUUAUGUAGAAAAAAUGCCAUCAAGUGAAAAUGAAAAAGCUGUAUCUCCAAAGAAGGCCUUACUUCCUCCUACAGUUUCUUUAUCUGCUACCUCAACUUCCUCUGAACCACUUUCUUCAAAUCAACCAGCAUCAGUGACUGAUUAUCAAAAUGUAUCUUUUUCAAACCUAACUGUAAAUACAUCAUGGCAGAAAAAAUCAGCCUUCACUCGAACUGUGUCCCCUGGAUCUGUAUCACCUAUUCAUGGACAGGGACAAGUGGUAGAAAACUUAAAAGCACAGGCCCUUUGUUCCUGGACUGCAAAGAAAGAUAACCACUUGAACUUCUCAAAACAUGACAUUAUUACUGUCUUGGAGCAGCAAGAAAAUUGGUGGUUUGGGGAGGUGCAUGGAGGAAGAGGAUGGUUUCCCAAAUCUUAUGUCAAGAUCAUUCCUGGGAGUGAAGUAAAACGGGAAGAACCAGAAGCUUUGUAUGCAGCUGUAAAUAAGAAACCUACCUCGGCAGCCUAUUCAGUUGGAGAAGAAUAUAUUGCACUUUAUCCAUAUUCAAGUGUGGAACCUGGAGAUUUGACUUUCACAGAAGGUGAAGAAAUAUUGGUGACCCAGAAAGAUGGAGAGUGGUGGACAGGAAGUAUUGGAGAUAGAAGUGGAAUUUUUCCAUCAAACUAUGUCAAACCAAAGGAUCAAGAGAGUUUUGGGAGUGCUAGCAAGUCUGGAGCAUCAAAUAAAAAACCUGAGAUUGCUCAGGUAACUUCAGCAUAUGUUGCUUCUGGUUCUGAACAACUUAGCCUUGCACCAGGACAGUUAAUAUUAAUUCUAAAGAAAAAUACAAGUGGGUGGUGGCAAGGAGAGUUACAGGCCAGAGGAAAAAAGCGACAGAAAGGAUGGUUUCCUGCCAGUCAUGUUAAACUUUUGGGUCCAAGUAGUGAAAGAGCCACACCUGCCUUUCAUCCUGUAUGUCAGGUGAUUGCUAUGUAUGACUAUGCAGCAAAUAAUGAAGAUGAGCUCAGUUUCUCCAAGGGACAACUCAUUAAUGUUAUGAACAAAGAUGAUCCUGAUUGGUGGCAAGGAGAGAUCAACGGGGUGACUGGUCUCUUUCCUUCAAACUACGUUAAGAUGACGACAGACUCAGAUCCAAGUCAACAGUGGUGUGCUGAUCUGCAAACCCUGGACACAAUGCAGCCAAUUGAGAGGAAAAGACAGGGCUAUAUUCAUGAGCUGAUUCAGACCGAAGAGCGGUACAUGGCUGACCUUCAGCUCGUCGUCGAGGUUUUUCAGAAACGCAUGGCAGAGUCAGGCUUUCUCACUGAAGGGGAGAUGGCCCUGAUUUUUGUUAACUGGAAGGAGCUCAUCAUGUCCAACACAAAGCUGCUGAAGGCUUUGCGGGUGCGGAAGAAGACCGGGGGCGAGAAGAUGCCGGUGCAGAUGAUUGGGGACAUCCUGGCCGCUGAGCUGUCCCACAUGCAGGCUUACAUCAGGUUCUGCAGCUGCCAGCUUAAUGGAGCAGCUCUGUUACAGCAGAAGACAGAUGAAGACACAGAUUUCAAAGAAUUUUUAAAGAAGCUGGCAUCUGACCCGCGGUGUAAAGGAAUGCCCCUCUCCAGCUUCCUGCUGAAACCCAUGCAGAGGAUCACCCGCUACCCACUGCUCAUCAGAAGUAUUCUGGAGAACACCCCGGAGAGCCAUGCAGACCAUUCCUCCCUAAAGCUGGCCCUCGAGCGGGCAGAGGAGCUGUGCUCUCAAGUGAAUGAGGGAGUUCGGGAGAAGGAAAACUCGGACCGACUGGAGUGGAUCCAGGCGCACGUGCAGUGUGAAGGCCUCGCGGAGCAACUUAUUUUCAACUCUCUCACCAACUGCCUGGGGCCCCGGAAGCUCUUACACAGUGGGAAAUUAUACAAGACCAAGAGCAACAAGGAACUGCACGGAUUCCUCUUCAAUGACUUCCUGCUUCUUACCUACAUGGUCAAGCAGUUUGCUGUUUCCUCUGGCUCUGAGAAACUUUUCAGCUCGAAGUCCAAUGCUCAAUUCAAAAUGUAUAAAACGCCCAUUUUCCUGAAUGAAGUCUUGGUGAAACUGCCCACAGACCCUUCCAGCGAUGAGCCUGUCUUCCACAUUUCCCACAUUGAUCGGGUCUACACCCUCCGAACAGACAACAUUAAUGAGAGGACCGCCUGGGUGCAGAAGAUCAAGGCGGCGUCUGAGCAGUACAUCGACACCGAGAAGAAGAAGCGUGAGAAAGCUUACCAAGCCCGCUCCCAAAAGACUUCAGGCAUUGGGCGCCUGAUGGUGCAUGUCAUUGAAGCUACAGAAUUAAAAGCCUGCAAACCAAAUGGAAAGAGCAACCCAUACUGUGAAAUCAGCAUGGGCUCCCAGAGCUACACCACCAGGACCAUCCAGGACACACUCAAUCCCAAGUGGAAUUUUAACUGCCAGUUCUUUAUUAAGGAUCUCUACCAAGACGUGCUGUGUCUCACCCUGUUUGACAGAGACCAGUUUUCACCAGAUGAUUUCCUGGGUCGUACUGAAAUUCCAGUGGCAAAAAUUCGAACAGAACAGGAAAGCAAAGGCCCUAUGACCCGCCGACUGCUGCUGCAUGAGGUCCCCACCGGGGAGGUCUGGGUCCGUUUUGACCUGCAGCUUUUUGAGCAAAAAACUCUCCUGUAGGGGUUCUAAAGGACAGCACCAGCGGGACAGCCCACAAGGCUGGGGCUGGAGAAUGAGAGACUGCGCUCUCUUGGGGCUGAGGGAGCACCAUGCAGCUUCACCCCUCACAAAGCCAUGCACGCUGGGGGCUCUGUUUUCCUGCACACUAAAUAGCUAGCAAUCUAUGCAAACACCUUUCCCAUAAAGAAACCAAACCCCAUAGUACAGUGCCUUGUCCUAGUGUUCACAUGUUCAGCUCUGUUUGUUUAGAUGCCAAGGUUUCCAUUUUCAGGGCUAUAAAAAGUAUUACUUGGAAAUGAGGCAUCAGACCACCAGAUGUUACCGCUCGGUUGAAUGUGUCCACCGUGGAGUGGUUUGGUGACGCUGUAACCAUUCCACGCCAGUGACCUCUGCUGGGUCACAGCCACUCAGGAGGGGAAGGGUCAGGAUGAGAGGCUGCAGCCUCGACACUUGGCGCGGCCUGAUACUGAAAUAGCGUCUACUCGUGCACUGAAUAAAAACAGAAACUUGAUCAUUUUAUUCCUGAUUAGAUUUUAUCACUCUCUGCUAAGACAAUAUAGUCUGGAGUAUAAGUGGGAAAGCUUGAUUUAAAUACUGUGAACUCUAAUAAUGUGGAAAAUAUUUUUCAACUUUAAUUUUCUGAAGUAUAAAUUAUUUAUGUAAAUUCAUUGUUUUUGCAUAUUUCUUAGGACAUGCAUCUUUAAGCUUUAUCAUUGCCCAUAUGUACAGAAAGAGAAUAAAGACAUAUGUUUAUGGAUGGAA